AGAGCGGAGCCUGUAGCCAGGCGCCAUCUUUGACGCUGGCAGUCUUGGUUUUCUGCUAGUGCUGCUGCUGCUGGGAGGACGACGGACGGCAGCGGCCAAGCAAGAAGAAAGACGUGGCAGCAAGCGGGAGUCGGGGAUAGUGUCAUCGGUUCGGUAAAGUUUCUGUUCUCUGGUAACUAGACCCGUUUUUUUGAUUCCCGGGUGGCUUGGGGCCGGGGAGGUGGGGGAGAGGGCGAGGGGAGUGGCAGCGGCCUCCCCUCGCCCCUGGGUCGCGGCCUAUCCCGGGAAGUCAGAGCGGAUCCUUCAGCUUCGCCGUAACGACCCCUCCCCCCCACCUCCCGGUCGCGGCCCUCGCCGGGGCUGGCUGGGAGCCCCAGGCUCCCGCUCACUUUUCCCAUCCUCCCCACCCCCACCCCGUUCACCCCACCCCCACGGCGCCUGCUCCUUUCCCAGCCAACCUUCCUCCCCUCCCCCACAUCCGGUGUUCGCUAAUCUCGAGGAGCCCGGAGCAGCCCCGAAAACCGACUGUUCCCCCGAAUCCCGAAGAGAGAACUGACACUAGAUUGCUUUCUUCGGGGCAACAGUUUCUCUAGUUGAGCGGACCCUCACUGCCUAAAUCAAUCAGACUGAGUGCCGGGCGCUGAAUUUACCUACUCUCAUUCCUCUCCAGGGUCCCGGUACUUUGGAGCUUGUCUCAAACUCCACAUACAGAAAGCCACCGACCUUAUUCCGGUAUCCUACACCCAUUCCCCACUCUCAUUACACUCCCACCCCUGGCCCUCAGCGUCGGAGUCAAGAGCAACAGGGACACUUCCGUUCUCCUUGUAGGACUGGUGAAACCGUAAUGAAGAACACCCCUAAACUCCCAUAAUCGGUGCGGAUUCCUAUGGGGAAGGCCUAUAUUGUUGACAUCUUCCAGGCCUUGGUUCUGGACCUUGAGAAAGAGGCUGUGGAACUAGAGAUAGCGAUGCUUUUUAGGGUAAAUGUAUGUAGGUAUUGGGGGAAGGGGAGGGAUCAAUCGAAAAAUGGAAGUGGUUUAAAGUUCAUAUUUCACUUUUUGCUAUCUCUAUAGCGUACAACUUGUGAGUUACUUACAGGCUGUAAAAGCUUCUCAAGUCUAAAAAUAUCUGAAAACUAAACUUGAAUUAACUCUUAAUACAAACAGUACUUUGAAAAUGCAGCAUUUAACCUUGUUUUAAAAUUUUUUUCUCAAAGCAUUUUUUUCCAGCCACUCACAUUUUAAAAGGUUGUAUUACUUUUAGUUAGAACUGAAAGGGCUCAACUAGCAUUUGCUGUGACCAGUAUGCGGAGUCUGUGUUGGCUUUCCAGAAUUGACUUUUUGGGUUGUAUUGGCAAAUCACAGUCCUAAAUGAUGAAUGUUGAAUGAUGCACUAUGUUUUUGUUUAAAUGAGAUUUCCUGAAAAUAGUUAAUUUCAGAAUUAAGGGAAAUUGAUGUCGCUAUCAUGAGGCAUCAUAAAAAUAUGUAUUUUACAAGGUGAAGGCAUUUCAAGUAGAUAUAGUUCUUGAUGAAGCAGGAAGAACAUGGAUCUGGGAUUUGGAAGACCUGGCUUCUAGCUGCUACUAACCAACUCUGUGACUCUGGGAAAGGGGGACUCAGUUCUUACUUCUGUAACAUGAGGACACUGGACUAUUUGAAUUCAGAACUUAGAAAAUUGGAAGGGACCUUAAAGCCCUCUAAGAAAGAGUUCGGGAAUGUUCUCCAUUGCUGUCAGUUUUCCUCCAAAAAUAACCUGGCUUGGAAGUUAUUGGUCCAGUGGGAAUUUGAUUCCCCAUAGAAACUGGAGAAAAGGUAAUGCAAGUAGAGAGGAACAGCUGUAUUUCUGCUUGAGUAAUAAACCCACUAACAGAUUCUGGUACGAAUUGUGGAGACAUAAAGAGAAUGAGUGUAUGUACUCUAAGUGUACCAGUUUCUUCACUCUCUCCUGGCAGAAGAUGCAACACUUUUAGUGAUUCUGGGAUUCUGGGAUGUGUUCCUAUUAAUUCUAAUACAGAUGAAGAAGAUGUGGUAGAGGAAAAGAUGGUAGCAGAAGGAGUGAAUAAAGAGGCAAAACAGCCUGCUAAAAAGAAAAGAAAGAAGGGUUUGCGAAUUAAGGGGAAAAGGCGUCGAAAAAAAUUGAUUCUUGCCAAAAAGUUUAGUAAGGAUUUGGGAUCUGGGAGGCCUGUUGCAGAUGCCCCUGCUUUGUUAGCUUCCAAUGACCCUGAGCAGGAUGAAGAAAGUCUUUUUGAGAGCAAUAUAGAAAAACAGAUCUAUCUACCUAGUACUAGAGCCAAGACCUCCAUUGUGUGGCACUUCUUUCAUGUUGACCCCCAGUACACCUGGCGGGCCAUUUGUAACCUCUGUGAGAAAAGCGUCAGCAGGGGUAAACCAGGUAGCCAUCUUGGUACAUCUACUCUUCAACGACAUCUGCAAGCAAGGCAUUCACCUCAUUGGACCAGGGCCAACAAGUUUGGAGUUGCUAGUGGAGAGGAGGACUUUACCUUGGAUGUGUCUUUAUCUCCCUCUUCUGGAAGCAAUGGAAGCUUUGAAUAUAUUCCUACUGAUCCAUUAGAUGAUAAUAGAAUGGGCAAGAAGCAUGAUAAAUCAGCAUCUGAUGCCCUAAGGGCAGAAAGAGGGAGAUUUCUCAUCAAAAGUAACAUUGUCAAGCAUGCUUUAAUUCCUGGAACUAGAGCCAAGACAUCUGCCGUUUGGAAUUUUUUUUACACUGAUCCUCAGCACAUCUCAAGAGCUGUGUGUAAUAUAUGUAAAAGAAGUGUGAGCCGGGGUAGGCCAGGGUCCCACUUAGGGACUUCAACACUUCAACGACACCUGCAAGCCACACAUCCUAUCCAUUGGGCUGUUGCCAACAAAGACAGUGGUGCUGUUGCAAAUGGAUUAGAUGAAGCUGAGACUGAGAGAAGUGAUCUCUUGAGUGAUACCUUGCAUGGAGAAAAGUCUACAGGCAGCCAAGAUUUAACAGCUGAGGACCUUAGUGACUCUGAUUCAGAUGAACCUAUGUUAGAGGUUGAAAACAGAUCUGAAAGUCCUAUUCCCGUUGCAGAGCAAGGCACUCUGAUGCGUGCGCAGGAGAGAGAAACAACAUGUUGUGGAAAUCCAGUCUCAAGUCACAUAAGUCAGGCAAUUAUCCAAAUGAUUGUGGAGGAUAUGCAUCCUUACAACUAUUUCUCAACCCCAGCCUUUCAGAGGUUCAUGCAGAUUGUGGCCCCUGAUUAUAGGUUGCCAUCAGAGACUUACUUUUUCACUAAGGCUGUACCUCAGUUAUAUGAUUGUGUCAGAGAAAAAAUUUUCUUAACUUUAGAGAAUGUUCAAAGCCAAAAGAUACACCUGACUGUUGACAUAUGGACCCAUGACCCAUCCACUGACUAUUUUAUUGUGACUGUACACUGGGUUUCUUUGGAAACUGCGUCUUUUCUCAAUAAUGGCAGGAUCCCCGAUUUUAGAAAGUGGGCAGUGCUUUGUGUUACAGGUUUGGCUAAAGACUGUUUGAUAACCAAUAUUUUACAAGAAUUAAAUGACCAGAUUGGUCUGUGGCUUUCUCCAAAUUUCCUUAUCCCUAGCUUCAUUGUUUCUGACAAUUCCUCUAAUGUGGUACAUGCAAUCAAAGAUGGUGGUUUUACCCAUGUGCCAUGCUUCCUGCAUUGUUUAAAUAUGGUCAUUCAGGACUUUUUCUGCGAGCACAAAAGCAUUGAGAAUAUGUUAGUGGCUGCCAGGAAAACUUGUCAUCAUUUUAGUCAUUCGGUCAAGGCCCGUCAGAUACUGCAAGAGUUCCAAAAUGAUCACCAACUUCCAUGGAAGAAUUUGAAGCAGGACGAAACUGGCCAUUGGAUUUCUACUUUUUAUAUGUUAAAAUGGCUCUUGGAGCAUUGCUACUCAGUUCACCAUAGUCUUGGUAGAGCCAGUGGAGUUGUGCUCACCUCCCUUCAGUGGACUCUAAUGACUUAUGUUUGUGAUAUUCUUAAGCCAUUUGAGGAGGCUACCCAGAAAGUGAGCGUGAAGACCGCAGGAUUGAAUCAGGUGCUACCCCUAAUCCAUCAUCUACUCCUUUCCCUGCAGAAACUCAGAGAAGAUUUUCAAGUCAGAGGUAUUACUCAGGCCCUCAAUCUGGUGGAUAGUUUAUCUCUGAAACUUGAAACAGAUACCCUACUAAGUGCCAUGCUUAAAUCCAAGCCCUGUAUCUUGGCUACUUUGUUAGAUCCUUGCUUUAAAAACAGUUUGGAAGACUUUUUUCCUCAAGGUGCUGAUUUAGAAACUUAUAAGCAGUUCCUUGCAGAAGAGGUCUGUAAUUAUAUGGAAUCUUCACCAGAGAUCUGCCAAAUUCCAACUUCAGAAGCUUCUUGUCCCUCAGUUACAGUGGGAGCUGAUUCAUUUACCUCAUCUCUAAAAGAAGGCACCUCCAGUUCAGGUUCUGUUGAUAGCUCAGCUGUAGACAAUGUUGCCCUUGGAAGCAAAAGCUUCAUGUUCCCUUCUGCUGUAGCAGUUGUGGAUGAGUACUUCAAAGAGAAGUAUUCAGAGUUCUCAGGAGGUGAUGACCCUUUAAUUUACUGGCAGAGGAAGAUAAGCAUAUGGCCGGCUUUGACCCAGGUUGCCAUCCAGUAUCUAAGUUGCCCCAUGUGUAGUUGGCAAUCUGAAUGUAUCUUUACUAAAAAUAGCCACUUUCAUCCAAAACAGAUCAUGAGCCUGGACUUUGACAAUAUAGAACAACUGAUGUUUCUGAAAAUGAACUUGAAAAAUGUUAACUACGAUUAUUCUACGUUGGUUCUGAGCUGGGAUCCUGAGCAGAAUGAAGUUGUUCAAAGCAGUGAAAAAGAAAUACUGCCUUAAUUUCUUUUUCUCCAUUUAAAAUGGGCAACUUUUUGCUGUGUUACUGUAUCUUAAUAGCUGUAGUUGUUAAAUAUAAUCAUUAUCUUUAUAAACACAUCUGGGGAAACCUGAAAUCACACAAGGGCUGAAAAUUCCUCAGAGGCAAUAUAAUUUUGAUAAAAUGAAGAUUAAAGAUUUCAUAGCUAUAACUGUGGCGCUAGCACUUGAAAAUUUUGCUUAUACCAAUGAGAGAGAAGAUAUUUUUAAUUAAAAAAAAUAUAGUGCAGCAUUGAAAGGCCUUAGGCUUUCUUCCUGGUAGAUUGAACUAGUAAUUGGUUUUAAGUAAAACUUCCCCCACCAUGGGAAAUUUUAUUGCUCUGAAAUCAACGAAAUGAGAAAAAAGUACACUGGCUGGCAUUCCUCCUGCCCCUGUUUUUCUGUUUCCUUAAAAACCCUGAUGCUUAAUUACAACUUGGCAAAAAGAAAACCCGUGAAAUUGUUUUAUAUUUGGAAAUUUCUAAUUGCCUCCUCAUACUGGUCAGCUUUAUAAUUUCAAAUUGUUGAGUGUGAUAGUGUUACCCUUUAGAAUUGGAUCUUAUAUAAAAGGGAAAUAUUAGAAAACAAUUAGGAAAAUAUACUUUUAGUCUUUGAAAUGCCUGUUUUAACCUUUAUAAAAUAUUAUAAAAAUAGAUUGUGUAGGUACUUUCAAAUAAUUUAUGGGUAAAAACAGACUAAAAUGUUUGCAAGAAUUGGAAAAGGUUGAAUGGGAAUUGUAAUGAGAGCCCUUUGAACAUGCUUGGAAAAACCCAGUAGACAUUUCCCAAAGAUUGUUUCUGUAAUUUUAGGUAAUCUUUUUAAAAACAUACUUAAUGACCCAUUAUACUGUAUUAACUGUGCGGUUGUUUUGGCCACUGAAUUCUUAAUGAAAACUAAGCAGUCGGUAUUUUUAUGUGUUAGGAAUCAUUGGUGAAAUGAGUGAAUUGAUCUCAUUUUAAGAUCCCUUUCUACUCUGAAAGUAUGUUUCUGAGAUUGAGUAGGAGGCCAGAAAAUGAUGACUUUUAGUAAAAGUCUAUUAAAAGUUUCAGACUGAAUAACUAAUGUGAGAUCCCAAUUUUUCCUUUUUUUCAUUUUAGAUUUGGGGAUAUUCCCUGCCCAAAAAAUUCCUGGAAAAUUGACUAGUAUUAAGUGUGAGUAAAAGGUGUCCACUUUUUUUUAAGUUUUGAUUUUAGUUUUGUCUUGGAUAGUAUUUGGCAAGAUUUAGCCUAGAAAUUAUGUAGUAUUUAUUACAUAAGAAUCAAAAUUGCUUUGUUACUGGGCUGGUUUCAAAGUUUAGAACUCAUUUCUAUGUAUCAAAAUCGGGUUUUUUUUGGUUUUGAUUUUUUUUUUUUUUAAAUUCUUAAAUGGUAAAUAUGCCAUUGUGAAAUGAAAUCUCAACUCCAAAAGUUUACCCUUUUACUAACUGGAGUAAAUGUAUACUUACAAAGUCUUUAGCUGUAGCCAUUAGUAGUAAAGAAUUUGGACCUAGGCUGCGUAAGCAAGCCUUUCCAGGGCCACUAUUUAAUGGCAAACCAGUGAUACUGGUGUUGAUACAAAAUAAGAAAUAAAUUUUCCCUUAGAUAAAGCUUUCUGUGUUUUGACAGUGCCAGUUUAGAAUGGCUAUAAUGCUGCUCUGCCUUCUACAGCUUGCUGCACCACUCUGUAGUUACUCUAUUACCAUACGUUUCUAUCUUUUUUGGUUAAACACUCCCUGAUGACGAUGAUGGAUAUAUAUACAUACAUCCAUAUUAUACAUAAUGAUAUAUGUGUAAGGAUUUACCUUCGUCUUUAUUUUGUGGGCUGGGCAAAAUUUAGUGUAACAAUAACUUCAUGAUACUUUGGUAUAAGAGUAAGUUCUUUAUUUUUAUAAUGAACCCAAAUCUAAAGUCUUUUAUAGUGCAUUUUAAAAGGGGAAACUUAUCCAAAUGUUAUAUUUCUAUACAUUUUUGUGUAUAUGUGUGUGUGUAUAAGCCAGUUAGUAUAUAUCUGUAUGUAUAUUAUAUACAUAAAACACUAUAUUUUUACAUACAAGUAUGCUUUUAUUAUACAGAUAAUAAAGAUGGGGGAAGGUUUCUGUUUUUUUCUUAAUAGGUGAAGAAAUCUUGAAGACCAGAAAUUGGAUCUUACUGAAAAACUGAUGUUUUUUUGUUUUUUUUUUAAAUUAUAUUGUUCAGCUAUGGAAGAUGGAGUUUUUUUUCAUGAUCCUUUAACUCUCAAGUUCAUCUUUAAAUGAACUCUUUUUUUUUGUUUUUUUUUUGUUUUGUUUUGUUUUGUUUUUGAGGAGAUAACUAACCCUAGCUGUCUCCAGUCUGACAAAGGUUAUUUGAAUGGACUUAAUCUCCCAGUAGUUGGGAGAUGUUUUAAAAACACAUGCUGUGUUUGAAUUGUGGCUGAGAGGUUUUCUUGGCAAUGUGAGGAGGAAAUUUUUUUCUGCCUCAUUAUUAUUAAUUCAUGGAUUGAGUGUUGGUUCGACCUACAGGCGUAAUAGAUUGGAACUCAGUGAAGACACAGAUGUUCCUGUUCAGAGCAACCAGCUAAUGAUUACAGUUUAAAGACAAUUUCUGUGAUCAAGUUGUCAUUUGGAAGAUUAAACCCAUUUCACGAGGACUUGGAGCCUGGUCCUUGCUUUGAGGAAGCAGUGGCUUGUUUCAAGAAGCCACUUCUGAUCUAAGAAUCUACCCAGCAUGCCUAAUCAAGGAGAAGACUGCUAUUUUUUUUUCUAUUCCACAUGUACCAAAGGUGACAGCUGCCCAUUCCGUCACUGUGAAGCUGCAAUAGGAAAUGAAACUGUUUGCACAUUAUGGCAAGAAGGGCGCUGUUUUCGACAGGUGUGCAGGUUUCGGCACAUGGAGAUUGAUAAAAAACGCAGUGAAAUUCCUUGUUAUUGGGAAAAUCAGCCAACAGGAUGUCAAAAAUUAAACUGCGCUUUCCAUCACAAUAGAGGACGAUAUGUUGAUGGCCUUUUCCUACCUCCGAGCAAAACUGUGUUGCCCACUGUGCCUGAGUCACCAGAAGAGGAAGUGAAGGCUAGCCAACUUUCAGUUCAGCAGAACAAAUUGUCUGUCCAGUCCAAUCCUUCCCCUCAGCUGCGGAGCGUUAUGAAAGUAGAAAGUUCCGAAAAUGUUCCUAGCCCCACGCAUCCACCAGUUGUAAUUAAUGCUGCAGAUGAUGAUGAAGAUGAUGAUGAUCAGUUUUCUGAGGAAGGUGAUGAAACCAAAACACCUACCCUGCAACCAACUCCUGAAGUUCACAAUGGAUUACGAGUGACUUCUGUCCGGAAACCUGCAGUCAAUAUAAAGCAAGGUGAAUGUUUGAAUUUUGGAAUAAAAACUCUUGAGGAAAUUAAGUCAAAGAAAAUGAAGGAAAAAUCUAAGAAGCAAGGUGAGGGUUCUUCAGGAGUUUCCAGUCUUUUACUCCACCCUGAGCCCGUUCCAGGUCCUGAAAAAGAAAAUGUCAGGACUGUGGUGAGGACAGUAACUCUCUCCACCAAACAAGGAGAAGAACCCUUGGUUAGAUUGAGUCUUACUGAGAGACUGGGGAAACGAAAAUUUUCAGCAGGCGGUGACAGUGAUCCUCCAUUAAAGCGUAGCCUGGCACAGAGGCUAGGGAAGAAAGUUGAAGCUCCAGAAACUAACAUUGACAAAACACCAAAGAAAGCUCAAGUUUCCAAGUCUCUUAAGGAGCGAUUAGGCAUGUCAGCUGAUCCAGAUAAUGAGGAUGCAACAGAUAAAGUUAAUAAAGUUGGUGAGAUCCAUGUGAAGACAUUAGAAGAAAUUCUUCUUGAAAGAGCCAGUCAGAAACGUGGAGAAUUGCAAACUAAACUCAAGACAGAAGGACCUUCAAAAACUGAUGAUUCUACUUCAGGAGCAAGAAGCUCCUCCACUAUCCGUAUCAAAACCUUCUCUGAGGUCCUGGCUGAAAAAAAACAUCGGCAGCAGGAAGCAGAGAGACAAAAAAGCAAAAAGGAUACAACUUGCAUCAAGCUAAAGAUUGAUAGUGAAAUUAAAAAAACAGUAGUUUUGCCACCCAUUGUUGCCAGCAGAGGACAAUCAGAGGAGCCUGCAGGUAAAACAAAGUCUAUGCAGGAGGUGCACAUCAAGACGCUGGAAGAAAUUAAACUGGAGAAGGCACUGAGGGUGCAGCAGAGCUCUGAGAGCAGCACCAGCUCCCCGUCUCAACACGAGGCCACUCCAGGGGCAAGGCGGCUGCUGCGAAUCACCAAAAGAACAGGGAUGAAAGAAGAGAAGAACCUUCAGGAAGGAAAUGAAGUUGAUUCUCAGAGCAGUAUUAGAACAGAAGCUAAAGAGGCUUCAGGUGAGACCACAGGAGUUGACAUCACUAAAAUUCAAGUCAAGAGAUGUGAGACCAUGAGAGAGAAGCACAUGCAGAAACAGCAGGAGAGGGAAAAAUCAGUCUUGACACCUCUUCGGGGAGAUGUAGCCUCUUGCAAUACCCAAGUGGCAGAGAAACCAGUGCUCACUGCUGUGCCAGGAAUCACACGGCACCUGACCAAGCGGCUUCCCACAAAGUCAUCCCAGAAGGUGGAGGUAGAAACCUCAGGGAUUGGAGACUCAUUAUUGAAUGUGAAAUGUGCAGCACAGACCUUGGAAAAAAGGGGUAAAGCUAAACCCAAAGUGAACGUGAAGCCAUCUGUGGUUAAAGUUGUGUCAUCCCCCAAAUUGGCCCCAAAACGUAAGGCAGUGGAGAUGCACGCUGCUGUCAUUGCCGCUGUGAAGCCACUCAGCUCCAGCAGUGUCCUACAGGAACCCCCAGCCAAAAAGGCAGCUGUGGCUGUUGUCCCGCUUGUCUCUGAGGACAAAUCAGUCACUGUGCCUGAAGCAGAAAAUCCUAGAGACAGUCUUGUGCUGCCUCCAACCCAGUCCUCUUCAGAUUCCUCACCCCCGGAGGUGUCUGGCCCUUCCUCAUCCCAAAUGAGCAUGAAAACUCGCCGACUCAGCUCUGCCUCAACAGGAAAGCCCCCACUCUCUGUGGAGGAUGAUUUUGAGAAACUAAUAUGGGAGAUUUCAGGAGGCAAAUUGGAAGCUGAGAUUGACCUGGAUCCUGGGAAAGAUGAAGAUGACCUUCUGCUUGAGCUAUCAGAAAUGAUUGAUAGCUGAAGGUGGUAGUGAGGACACUUUAAAAAAAAAAUCGCCAAAAAACUGGACUUAGUUUCAUCUAUUGUAACAUUUACCUGAGAUGAUCAUUUCUUUAGUCUAGAAUUUGCCCCAAAUCAGAAGUAUACCUCUGAAUUAUCUGUAUGUGUCCUGGAUUCCUUGGGGUCAGAUUUUUAAAGUUACUUUAUAACCAUUUUGUCCAUUUGAUGCCAUUGUUUAUCAUCUUUUGAGAAAAAAGUUCUGUCAUACCCUUCUCUCCACAAAAAAGAGACUGAGAGGGAGAUCAAGUGAAAGGGUGCAAGCGAACUUAGUGACUCCUUGAGGUGUUUGUCAGUUUUGGCUUUUUUCUUCUUUGUUGUAUUCUUUAUGUAUUGUCUUGAUGUACUUAAUAUUACCUGAGUUUGAAAUGGAUGAAGACAGCUGCUACCAUUAAGGACCAAAUUUUAUGCUACCACUAAACAAAAAUACCCACUCAGUCUGUGUUAAAUUGUAUGUCUUUUUAAAGGUAUUUAAAGAUUCAACUAAGCUUUAAAGAGGGCUGAGCAGCUCAGGAAGCCUGUAAUGUGGGCAUAACUCUUUGGACCUGAUCUUGAUGCUUCUGCUGCUCUGUUAGCCUCUGAAGAGCAAUAUCUAAUUUAUUAUUACUGUAAUUUUUUAAAAGGCUUUAAAGUGCCUCAGGGGUCCCCUGAAACUAAUUUUCUAUUUCUGGGAUUCCCUGGAUUCAUUAUAUGAGAUGGUGACAUGAUUAGAGGAAUUCUUUUUUAGUAUGAAAAUUGUCCUUUUUCUUCUUCAGUACUUGCCUCCUUGCUGGCAUUGAAUUAACACAGGGACAAAAUUUGGUUAAUUUUUUAUUUCUAACUCUCCCAACAAACCCCUGUUGCCCAGUAUUUGUUUGGUGGCCUUUAACCACCUGAGGGAAAAAAUGAGCUUAUUCAAGCUGCCAAUAUUUAUCUAUGGGCUGUAGCAGUACACUGAAUUGUACUGUGCCAGGGAUAUUGAGAUGCUCUGGGGGUGUAUUGUAUACCUGCCAGUUUUCUUCAUUUCUGAAUUGAGUUUUCUUUUCUUGAUGUUGGUUUCCUUCAUAUCACCUCAAGGUUUAGAUUUGUGAAGGAAUAAGCAUGAUGGAAAUAAUAGUCUUGAAAGGAGAUAUGUUGUAUAUAAUCAGGAGGAAGAGGAAGGAAGGACUUACCCAUUUUGAUAUUUUGCUGUAGGUGGCCAGUUUUGUUUCUCAUAGGGAAAUCUGACCCACCUGUCAUGUUGGCUCCUAAGGAACUGCUGUUGUAAGCGGCUCAUCAAGAGUUGAACUUCACGUAGCCUUGUUGGGAAUAUGGAAAAGGAAGAAAGCCACAGGACUGCCCAUUCAGUCUUGGGAAGAUUGGGAUGAUUCUGCACAAGCAAAAAUGACUGAAGUUUAUGUAUAGACACACCUCUACCAAUCCAUCUUCAGCUGACUGAAUGUUGUAUGAUAGCCCUUCUCCAAAGCAGAGGUAGAAUGUUCAGGUUUCACCAUGGAUUUUCUACUUAUUUCGUUUUUGGAAUCAGCUUACAGAUUCCAGGUCCCUUUUGUAUAUAUUCUUUAUUCUUUUGCUUUUUUAAAAAAUAAUUUUGUUUCAUAUUUAAAGCACUUGUAUUAGUCAAUGUUUCGUGUUCCGCAUUAUUUGAACCAUUUGCCCUUACAGAAAGAGAAAUACUUGUUUGUGUUUUAAAUAAAACUGAUGUAGGAAAGUC